GUCUUUGCGCUCGGACCUUCGCCAGAGGGGCCGGGACAUCAUGACGGUGGGAGCCAGGCUCCGAAGCAAGGCGGAGAGCAGCCUCCUGCGCCGCGGGCCCCGAGGGCGAGGGCGAACCGAGGGGGACGAGGAGGCGGCCGCCAUCCUGGAGCACCUGGAGUACGCGGACGAGGCGGAGGCGGCGGCCGAGAGCGGGACGAGCGCGGCGGACGAGCGGGGCCCGGGGACCCGGGGCGCGCGGAGGGUGCACUUCGCCCUCCUGCCCGAGCGCUACGAGCCACUGGAGGAGCCGGCGCCGAGCGAGCAGCCCAGGAAGAGGUACCGGAGGAAGCUGAAGAAGUACGGCAAGAAUGUCGGGAAGGUCAUCAUCAAAGGAUGCCGCUACGUGGUCAUCGGCCUGCAAGGCUUCGCUGCAGCCUACUCCGCCCCGUUUGCGGUAGCCACCAGCGUGGUAUCCUUCGUGCGCUAAUGGGAGCUGCUGUGGCAGGUGCCCCCAGAGUGAACGGGAGCCCCUGCUGUGGGAACUUUGUGAAUCCUGGAGCAUCUCAGACUUGAACACACAGCAUAUUUGGAAGAGAAAACAUGCCUUUCUUUGUUGAAUCACAUUAGUAUGAUGAGUGAGUCAUCCCUGCCCAUCUGCUGAGCUUCUCACAUCUCUCAGUCACACGUGGACCCAGUGGUCAAUCCUGCAGAGAAUUCGGCGGAGGUUAGGUUUGGGAGUGGAGCUAGCGUGCUAAAGCCAGAGCCUUCACGUGAAGGUGGCAGGCACUGGGGCGGAAGCCAACACUCAACAGAUGCAAGCAGUGUGGGUGUGCAGCAGAACAGUGAUCUUGGGGGAGGAAGAGGAUGUUACUAGAGUCAGAUGAUUUGCUGUAUUCUCCUGAAAGGUCGUAGGCUGACAGGCGCUCACAUUCCUUGGCUGCCUCGGUUCUGAGGGCAGCUAAGGAGCUGUUUAUUCCUCAAGUCAUGCUCCCCGAUCUCCUUCCUCUACCACUCUGUCACCAGGAGUUUAAUUACAGGCUUGAGGAGAAGAAAGGAAGAAAAGAUAUCUUGAUGCUUUGAAAACUGUGUUGGCAGUGUGGCAUGACUGUUUAAAGUAGAUAAAACCUUGUCAUUUUACCCCAUCCCUGCAUGACUGUGAAGCUGGCGAGGAAGGAGGAAGAAGGGCAAGUUCAGAUGCAGGCUGGGUGGCUGGGACAGGUUGGCUAAGGGACUACUCUGGAGGGCUCUUCUGCCUGGCAUUGCCCACUUCGGCCCAGCCACGUGUUUGCAGCGACCAGAGUCCCUGCAAAGGUGUGGCUGGCUGUGGUCAGGGUGCUACUAGCACCAUCAGCGCACUCCCGCCAUUGGCUCAGCUCCUCUCUGCCAGUCCAACUAAGAGUGCUUUGUCCUGGGUGGGACAUAGGGGCUGAGAGAGAUGGGGGGAGACAUAACACCCAGGAAUGAAAAUACAGAUUUAGAGAAGGAACCAGUAAGUAGGAGACAGAUGUGAAGGAAAUGGAAAUGAGGCAAGAGGACAUUGGAAGAGAGAAGUUUGCUGUCCAGGAGCCAGGUCUGGAGCAUCAGUGUGAGGGAGUUCAGGUAGGCUGGGCCUGUGCCUCUAGGUAGGGACAAGGGAGGCUGGGUAGCCAGGGCUGGUGCUUAAAACCCCUGAGGCCAUGAGCUCAUUGGCUGCCUUUGUAGCAUCCUGUCUUCUUCUGUGCUGCCUGGUUUGAUCUCAUCUCACCUGGAUUCAAAGGGUAAGGUGGGCAUGGGUCUUGGGCCUGACACCCACCAAGGAUGACCUGUGGACUGCCAUCGGAUGCUGAACAGGGAGAUGAAAGGAGGUCCUCUUACCAUACCCCUCUGCCAACCCCCCAGUAGGCCACUGUUCUGACUUUGUUUCCAGAAUAUCCAGAAAUCCAAAGGGGCUGUUGCUGAACAGUCUGCAGGACCAGUGACAGCACCUACCUGUUGUCCCAAGGCAUACAAAGGAGGCCUCAACGCUCAUGCUUCUCUAAUCAAGCCCUACCAAGACAGACAGAAAGACAGACAGAAAAAAGGAAGGGGUAGAGGAGAAGGUUGAAGCUGUGGAGCUAGACUCUGCUUCACUUCCUGAAGCUUCAACUUCAUGUCGAAGAUUCACUGGGACCCAAUUCCUGCAUUGUUAAUAUUUGUGAGGAAAAGUGAAACAAGUGAUCUGGUUUUAGCCCAGAUGAUGAAAGUGGAUAUGGCACAUUUUCACACACGUGAGAUAAUUACAGCUUGCCCCACAACACUGGGUGUUGGAGAAAGGGAGAGAUAGUCAUAAGUGGAAGAAAAAGCCAAGCAUAGUGAGUGGGAAAGAGAGUGAGAGCCUGUGCAGGCUGCUGACGAGCCCCAGGCAGCCCACAAGUUUCUCGUGGGGAGAUGGAGGCAGAGCCCAGGGUAGGGGACAGAGCUGCUGGGGCCUUUCCUUGCCUGGGAAUCUGUCCCAGGAAGAGCUUCCCCACUCCCAUCCCCCAAAUUGGAAAAACCGUACAUUCAAGCCUGUUUGGCCCUGAAAUUCUUAAGAAUCUGGUUAAGAAUUAACUCACUAAUGUCAAAAGUCAAAACCUCCUAGGGGUUGUCCUGGGAGUCAGGUUCACGGGUACAGAAGAUGAAUCUCAGAUGUCACUCAACCUGAGCCGUCAUUCUCUGUGGCAGGGCUGCCCUGGGUUUCUCUUACUCAAUCCCUGGAGUGUAAGCAUUUGGAUUGUGUCACAGAUUACCUUUUUACCUUUUCUUUCUUUUUUUUUCUUUUUUUCAAUAUCAGUGCCCACACCUUACUGAGUAUUGAGUUUUAGAGCUUUCGCUUGAUGUGCUUGACCAAGAGACUUCUUUUGUAUCCUUUUCUUGUCCUAUGAUGUAAAUAAAAGCCUCGAUUUAUGUAA